AACUCCUUUACCCUACAUGCCUGAGAAGCCAGGGACCAAGAUGGAUCUUCUCCUCGACAUCAGCUAAGCCUGGAGGACUCUUCCCCUCAGAGACCAUGGAGAGGGACAGCCACGGGAAUGCAUCUCCAGCAAGAACACCUUCAGCUGGAGCAUCUCCAGCCCAGGCAUCUCCAGCUGGGACACCUCCAGGCCGGGCAUCUCCAGCCCAGGCAUCUCCAGCCCAGGCAUCUCCAGCUGGGACACCUCCGGGCCGGGCAUCUCCAGCCCAGGCAUCUCCAGCUGGUACACCUCCAGGCCGGGCAUCUCCAGGCCGGGCAUCUCCAGCCCAGGCAUCUCCAGCCCAGGCAUCUCCAGCCCGGGCAUCUCCGGCUCUGGCAUCACUUUCCAGGUCCUCAUCCGGCAGGUCAUCAUCCGCCAGGUCAGCCUCGGUGACAACCUCCCCAACCAGAGUGUACCUUGUUAGAGCAACACCAGUGGGGGCUGUACCCAUCCGAUCAUCUCCUGCCAGGUCAGCACCAGCAACCAGGGCCACCAGGGAGAGCCCAGGUACGAGCCUGCCCAAGUUCACCUGGCGGGAGGGCCAGAAGCAGCUACCGCUCAUCGGGUGCGUGCUCCUCCUCAUUGCCCUGGUGGUUUCGCUCAUCAUCCUCUUCCAGUUCUGGCAGGGCCACACAGGGAUCAGGUACAAGGAGCAGAGGGAGAGCUGUCCCAAGCACGCUGUUCGCUGUGACGGGGUGGUGGACUGCAAGCUGAAGAGUGACGAGCUGGGCUGCGUGAGGUUUGACUGGGACAAGUCUCUGCUUAAAAUCUACUCUGGGUCCUCCCAUCAGUGGCUUCCCAUCUGUAGCAGCAACUGGAAUGACUCCUACUCAGAGAAGACCUGCCAGCAGCUGGGUUUCGAGAGUGCUCACCGGACAACCGAGGUUGCCCACAGGGAUUUUGCCAACAGCUUCUCAAUCUUGAGAUACAACUCCACCAUCCAGGAAAGCCUCCACAGGUCUGAAUGCCCUUCCCAGCGGUAUAUCUCUCUCCAGUGUUCCCACUGCGGACUGAGGGCCAUGACCGGGCGGAUCGUGGGAGGGGCGCUGGCCUCGGAUAGCAAGUGGCCUUGGCAAGUGAGUCUGCACUUCGGCACCACCCACAUCUGUGGAGGCACGCUCAUUGACGCCCAGUGGGUGCUCACUGCCGCCCACUGCUUCUUCGUGACCCGGGAGAAGGUCCUGGAGGGCUGGAAGGUGUACGCGGGCACCAGCAACCUGCACCAGUUGCCUGAGGCAGCCUCCAUUGCCGAGAUCAUCAUCAACAGCAAUUACACCGAUGAGGAGGACGACUAUGACAUCGCCCUCAUGCGGCUGUCCAAGCCCCUGACCCUGUCCGCUCACAUCCACCCUGCUUGCCUCCCCAUGCAUGGACAGACCUUUAGCCUCAAUGAGACCUGCUGGAUCACAGGCUUUGGCAAGACCAGGGAGACAGAUGACAAGACAUCCCCCUUCCUCCGGGAGGUGCAGGUCAAUCUCAUCGACUUCAAGAAAUGCAAUGACUACUUGGUCUAUGACAGUUACCUUACCCCAAGGAUGAUGUGUGCUGGGGACCUUCGUGGGGGCAGAGACUCCUGCCAGGGAGACAGCGGGGGGCCUCUUGUCUGUGAGCAGAACAACCGCUGGUACCUGGCAGGUGUCACCAGCUGGGGCACAGGCUGUGGCCAGAGAAACAAACCUGGUGUGUACACCAAAGUGACAGAAGUUCUUCCCUGGAUUUACAGCAAGAUGGAGAGCGAGGUGCGAUUCAGAAAAUCCUAACCAGCUGGCCUGCUGCUCUGCACAGCACCGGCUGCUGUGAAGACUCUGGCCAUGGUGACUGGCCAUGUGUGGCAUCAUCUGGGCUAAUGGCCACCGGGCACCAUCGGACUCCCACCUCCACUGUCUGCUGCCUCUGUGUGUGUGUGUGUGUGUGUGUGUGUGUGUGCAUAUGUGUGCAUUGCCACUCUCCCAAGUUUUUCAGAAACCAGCAGAGCUGUCAACUCUUCUCAAAAUCCCAGGCUGGAAAUUACCUGGAGACAAGAGUUGAGUACCGUGGAUGUUCCUACAGGAGUGUCCAUAGAUGGAUGGAGGAGGUGGAGCCCAGAGCCCAAGGAAGAGCUGGGAAUUCUUGCUUCUCUGACCCUCACUUACAGACUAGCCCAGUGUGGGCAGAUGCCAGCGGCCCAGGUGGCGCCAUUGCUGUCCUGGGAUGGAUCGUGGGUUUUGGUGGAUGCAGCUUCCCAGGGCCUGGACCGUCUUCGGUGAAAAGCUGCUCCCGUUGGCUUUAUGAGCAUCAAGUCCUCACCCAGACCCCCUGCUGGUGCCGUGGAUGUCACCAGUCGGACUGUGCUGUGGCUAACCAGGCUGACAACUGAGAUGAGGAUUCACUGUACUCAUUUGGUCACAAGCUGCUGGGGCGGGUUUUAUUUUAUUUUAUUUUUAUAUUUAAGAAAUGAAAAUACGGGUAUUUUUAAAGAUUCUCCAAAAAGUCCAGAAGCCUUGACAGCUGGCAUCAAUCAGCCCAAGACCCCCAGGGGAUUCAUGGGAAAUGUCGUAUUUUAGAGUCCUACAGAAUAUUUCUGGCCUCAAGGAACUGGAUGAAGAGACUGGACAAAGUCCCCAGGAUGGGCAUCCCCCAAGUCACUACAGCAUCUGGAGCCCCUAGGAGAUACUCAGGGAAGCAAAUCCUUGUUUGGGCUGGCAAGCAAAUCCGACACGACGAGGUCCACAAACUGUUUCUGCAUCCCAGGGCUCUGACGAAGGCGUUAAGAAACAGAUGCUGUUCCCGCGUAGGCUCCCAGGGGCCCCAGGGAGGUCCAGGUGGACUGCCUCUCUCAUUCCCAGUAGCUGUCCUGGGACUUUGGGAUUUCUUCUCAGCUUUCUCCACCUUUCAGUUUCUCAGUUGUUUCAGAAACAUAGCAAUGACAUAAAAACUGCUAUGGAGAGAAAGCUAACAUGGUCCCAUGCCUUCCAGGCAGCCCUGCUGAAGGAUCUAAGUUGGCCCUGUUCCUGCAAAUCAUCAACGUGCCUGGACUCGCCAGCUAAAAGCCUGGGCCUUCCCCAGCCUUUUUUCUGGGGCACCUAUUCCUCUGCCAGUCCUGCUCCCCUCACCUUCCUUGGGCCCGUCAGAGUCUUUUGUGGUGCUGUGCUUCUCAGAGGCAGGAUCCAAGCAGAUCAGCCCAGCCUAGCCCAGCUCAGGCAGGCCAUGGCCGCUCAAGGGAAAGACUGCCCCAGAAGAGCAAGCUGGAGAGGCUGGGCAGGGGCUGAUGGGGCUGGGUACACUGGGGAAUGUUAGCAAGACUGGGAAGGAGGCCACAUUCCUGUCUGCAGCAGCCGCCAGCGAUGGUCUUCAGCAAUAAAAGUUGUGUGACCUGAGA